AUUACUACUGAAGGAAGAACGUGAGUAGGUUAGGAUUUCGGUUGAGAGGCUUGGGGUCUUGCGUUUCGCCCACCAUCUCCUGGGGACAGGGUGGAGUCGAUAUCCGGGACGGGGGGGAGGUUGCGGUGCCCCUCAGGGCUACCUCUCAAGAGUGCUAUCAUUUCCGCAGGCCAGAUCAGAAAAGGGAGCUCAGGUACCUUCCAGAGAGUGAGACCCAGCGCCCUUGUCUCGCACCCAGUAGGCUUUCAUCCCCGCCAUGGCGGAGCUGAUCCAGAAGAAGCUACAGGGAGAAGUGGAGAAAUAUCAACAGCUACAGAAGGACUUAAGUAAAUCCAUGUCGGGGAGGCAGAAACUUGAAGCACAACUAACAGAAAAUAAUAUCGUGAAAGAGGAACUGGCCCUGCUGGAUGGGUCCAACGUGGUCUUUAAACUUCUGGGUCCGGUGCUAGUCAAACAGGAGCUGGGGGAGGCUCGGGCCACAGUAGGGAAGAGGCUGGACUAUAUCACAGCUGAAAUUAAGCGAUACGAAUCCCAGCUUCGGGAUCUUGAGCGGCAGUCAGAGCAACAGAGGGAGACCCUUGCUCAGCUGCAGCAGGAGUUCCAGCGGGCCCAGGCAGCAAAGGCAGGGGCUCCUGGCAAGGCCUGACCCCAUGGUGGGGGGAGGGGAGGGGAGGGGAGGGAAUGAGGCAGCUCUAGGAUCUAUACUGUAGCUAAUAAAAUGUAAAAACACCUGG